GUUCGCGCCGGGCGCCCGCGUCGCCGGUGUCCGCGAGCCGCGGCGGGGCCGGCUGGGCUGCUCGCAUCACUUGGCGCCCGGCGCGGCGAGCGCUACCCGCGGCCCCCGCGCGGCCCUCCCCACAAAGGGCCGCGGAGCUGCGUGGCCGCCGCCGCCGGCCGUGGCUCGCCUCCGCGGGCGCGGAAAUUUGUUGCACUUCUUGGGGCUUUGUUUAUUUGUUUGUUUUUUCUCUGGGUUUCUUAUUUUUUUCGUUAUUUUGGACAAAAUGUCGGUCCGUGAUAUAAAAAUUGAGCGAGGAACCUUGGUGGCAUUGGGAGCUUUGCAGAAGGUGCAGUUUGAAUUCUGCUUUUCCCAGGGUGGCAGCUCGGUCUUGGCCGGAUGAAUCUUCGCUGCUGGCCGUGGAAACAGCUAGAGCAGCUCUUUUCCAAGAGAUAACUUCACCAAGAUGUCCAGUGAUAGGCAAAGGUCCGAUGAUGAGAGCCCCAGCACCAGCAGUGGCAGUUCAGAUGCGGACCAGCGAGACCCAGCCGCUCCAGAGCCUGAAGAACAAGAGGAAAGAAAACCUUCUGCCACCCAGCAGAAGAAAAACACCAAACUCUCUAGCAAAACCACUGCUAAGUUAUCCACUAGUGCUAAAAGAAUUCAGAAGGAGCUAGCUGAAAUAACCCUUGAUCCUCCUCCUAAUUGCAGUGCUGGGCCUAAAGGAGAUAACAUUUAUGAAUGGAGAUCAACUAUACUUGGUCCACCGGGUUCUGUAUAUGAAGGUGGUGUGUUUUUUCUGGAUAUCACAUUUUCAUCAGAUUAUCCAUUUAAGCCACCAAAGGUUACUUUCCGCACCAGAAUCUAUCACUGCAACAUCAACAGUCAGGGAGUCAUCUGUCUGGACAUCCUUAAAGACAACUGGAGUCCCGCUUUGACUAUUUCAAAGGUUUUGCUGUCUAUUUGUUCCCUUUUGACAGACUGCAACCCUGCGGAUCCUCUGGUUGGAAGCAUAGCCACUCAGUAUUUGACCAACAGAGCAGAACACGACAGGAUAGCCAGACAGUGGACCAAGAGAUACGCAACAUAAUUCACAUAAUUUGUAUGCAGUGUGAAGGAGCAGAAGGCAUCUUCUCACUGUGCUGCAAAUCUUUAUAGCCUUUACAAUACGGACUUCUGUGUAUAUGUUAUACUGAUUCUACUCUGCUUUUAUCCUUUGGAGCCUGGGAGACUCCCCAAAAAGGUAAAUGCUAUCAAGAGUAGAACUUUGUAGCUGUAGAUUAGUUAUGUUUAAAACGCCUACUUGCAAGUCUUGCUUCUUUGGGAUAUCAAAAUGUAUUUUGUGAUGUACUAAGGAUACUGGUCCUGAAGUCUACCAAAUAUUAUAGUGCAUUUUAGCCUAAUUCAUUAUCUGUAUGAAGUUAUAAAAGUAGCUGUAGAUGGCUAGGAAUUAUGUCAUUUGUAUUAAACCCAGAUCUAUUUCUGAGUAUGUGGUUCAUGCUGUUGUGAAAAAUGUUUUACCUUUUACCUUUGUCAGUUUGUAAUGAGAGGAUUUCCUUUUACCCUUUGUAGCUCAGAGAGCACCUGAUGUAUCAUCUCAAACACAAUAAACAUGCUCCUGAAGGCA